AACCCGGAAGUUGGCGCAGCGCGGUUGCCAAUGGUCGCUCCCUGAGAGGAUGCCGCUCGUGGUGUUUUGCGGGCUGCCGUACAGCGGCAAGAGCCGGCGUGCUGAAGAGUUGCGCGUGGCGCUGGCUGCCGAGGGCCGCGCGGUGUACGUGGUGGACGACGCAGCUGUCCUGGGCGCAGAGGACCCAGCGGUGUACGGCGAUUCUGCCCGUGAGAAGGCAUUGCGUGGAGCUCUGCGAGCCUCCGUGGAACGGCGCCUGAGUCGCCACGACGUGGUCAUCCUGGACUCGCUUAACUACAUCAAAGGUUUCCGUUACGAGCUCUACUGCCUGGCACGGGCGGCGCGCACCCCGCUCUGCCUGGUCUACUGCGUACGGCCCGGCGGCCCGAUCGCGGGACCUCAGGUGGCGGGCGCGAACGAGAACCCUGGCCGGAACGUCAGUGUGAGUUGGCGGCCACGCGCUGAGGAGGACGGGAGAGCCCAGGCGGCGGGCAGCAGCGUCCUCAGGGAACUGCAUACUGCGGACUCUGUAGUAAAUGGAAGUGCCCAGGCCGACGUACCCAAGGAACUGGAGCGAGAAGAAUCCGGGGCUGCGGAGUCUCCAGCUCUUGUGACUCCGGAUUCAGAGAAAUCUGCAAAGCAUGGGUCCGGUGCCUUUUACUCUCCCGAACUCCUGGAGGCCCUAACGCUGCGCUUUGAGGCUCCCGAUUCUCGGAAUCGCUGGGACCGGCCUUUAUUCACUUUGGUGGGCCUAGAGGAGCCGUUGCCCCUGGCGGGGAUCCGCUCUGCCCUGUUUGAGAACCGGGCCCCACCACCCCAUCAGUCUACGCAGUCCCAGCCCCUCGCCUCCGGCAGCUUUCUGCACCAGUUGGACCAGGUCACGAGUCAAGUACUGGCCGGAUUGAUGGAAGCGCAGAAGAGCGCUGUCCCCGGGGACUUGCUCACGCUUCCUGGUACCACAGAGCACUUGCGGUUUACCCGGCCCUUGACCAUGGCAGAACUGAGUCGCCUUCGUCGCCAGUUUAUUUCGUACACUAAAAUGCAUCCCAACAAUGAGAACUUGCCGCAACUGGCCAACAUGUUUCUUCAGUAUUUGAGCCAGAGCCUGCACUGACCAGAGGAGGUAGGGGGGAAGCCAUGGCUUCUGAUCUCCACUCCACUUUAUUUCUCUGGGAAAAAUAGGCUGCAGGUCUCCAGAGCAUAUCGAUGCAGUACUGUACUAGAGCUGUUGUGACUGAUUCACUCAAACUUUCCUGCAUACCCCUGUGCCAGGCCUUGGGUUUACAGCAUAAGUUCAGACUAAAGAGAAUGGAGAACUAUUGUGGUGCAACCUGGCAAAUCCCUCAGAGGACAGAGCUAAGGUGGACAGGGAUUACCUAGAUUGGAUCCUACUUGGGCUAUCACAGAGCAUUGACCAUUGGCUUCCCUCAUCUGAGGCGUGGGAGAGCAGACUGGAUAGAUGAGAAUUGUUUUAAAACAAUUGUGAACAGAAACUGAAGAUGGUACAGUUCUACAUCUGCACCUGCCCUUUUUUCAUACCACAAAAGUAUUUUUUGAGUACUGUACUGACUUUUUGCUAGUUUCUAUUCUGGGACCGAGUUCACAGAUAAAUCCAUUGGUUUGUAUCCUUGAGAAACUUUGUUUUUGUGGAAGUAAGAAAGUUAUCUACUAGAUUAUUUCCUCUAAUAAAAUCUUUUAAAAUAGUCUA